ACUCACGUUGCGGCCUUCCUCGCGUCACAGCCGGGAUGAAGCCGAUCCUACUGCAGGGCCAUGAGCGGUCCAUUACGCAGAUUAAGUAUAACCGCGAAGGAGACCUCCUCUUUACUGUGGCCAAGGACCCUAUCGUCAAUGUAUGGUACUCUGUGAAUGGUGAGAGGCUGGGCACCUACAUGGGCCAUACCGGAGCUGUGUGGUGUGUGGACGCUGACUGGGACACCAAGCAUGUCCUCACUGGCUCAGCUGACAACAGCUGUCGUCUCUGGGACUGUGAAACAGGAAAGCAGCUGGCCCUUCUCAAGACCAAUUCGGCUGUCCGGACCUGCGGUUUUGACUUUGGGGGCAACAUCAUCAUGUUCUCCACGGACAAGCAGAUGGGCUACCAGUGCUUUGUGAGCUUUUUUGACCUGCGGGAUCCGAGCCAGAUUGACAACAAUGAGCCCUACAUGAAGAUCCCUUGCAAUGACUCUAAAAUCACCAGUGCUGUUUGGGGACCCCUGGGGGAGUGCAUCAUCGCUGGCCAUGAGAGUGGAGAGCUCAACCAGUAUAGUGCCAAGUCUGGAGAGGUGUUGGUGAAUGUUAAGGAGCACUCCCGGCAGAUCAACGACAUCCAGUUAUCCAGGGACAUGACCAUGUUUGUGACCGCGUCCAAGGACAACACAGCCAAGCUUUUUGACUCCACAACUCUUGAACAUCAGAAGACUUUCCGGACAGAACGUCCUGUCAACUCAGCUGCCCUCUCCCCCAACUAUGACCAUGUGGUCCUGGGCGGUGGUCAGGAAGCCAUGGAUGUAACCACAACCUCCACCAGGAUUGGCAAGUUUGAGGCCAGGUUCUUCCAUUUGGCCUUUGAAGAAGAGUUUGGAAGAGUCAAGGGUCACUUUGGACCUAUCAACAGUGUUGCCUUCCAUCCUGAUGGCAAGAGAGGAAGGUGCCAAAAGAGGAGGCAUAGGCGUGCCCAAACAGCGCCAACAGUAGCCCUUCCCCAAACUCCAAUGACAGUGGGAACCGGCAGCCCAGCUGCCACACGCAGUCCAGGAAGAGGAGAAAGUCAGCGGCAGCCGUCCAGCCGACUCAGCCAGUUGUCCAUGCUUUGCUCCGAGUCCCCACAGGCCUCCACCAGGCGCAUGAAGCUCUCCUGCAGGGGACGCCCUCUGGGCGGUGGGAGUCUGGUCAUCUUUUCCAGCUCAAGCCCUUGCCAAGUACAGCCAGGGAGCAAGUGCUCAAGACCAAUGAGGGAGACACAGAAUCCUGUAAAGAGCCCAUCUGAUAAAAGGGACACAGAGCCCUUUAGGGAGUCCAGUCUCACGGCACACACGACCCACAGAGGAGUUCCUAAUCUUUGAGACAGCGUCUCGUUCUGUCCAUGAAAUGGUUUUUUUUUUUUUUUGAGACGGAAUCUUGCUCUGUCUCCAGGCUGGAGUGCAGUGGUGCGAUCUCAGCUCACUGCAACCUCCGCCUCCCGGGUUUAAGUGAUUCUUCUGCCUCAGCCUCCAGAGUAGCUGGGACUACAGGCGACCGCCACCACACCCAGCUAGUUUUUGCAUUGUUAGGUUUCACCAUGUUGGCCAGAAUGGUCUCGGACUCCUGACCUUGUGAUCCGCCCACCUCGGCCUCCCAAAGUGCUGGGAUUACAGGCAUGAGCCACCGCGCCCAGCCUAAAAUGGUUUCUUAGCUUUGAGGAUUCCUCAGUCUGAUGGGAGAGACUCAAGACCCUUUGAGAAAGUACCUGGGGAAGGGUCACAUAGCCCUCUGGGGAAACACACAAUGUCCUGGGAAACCACCAAUUUGAUGGAAGUAUCACAACACCCUUGAUGUACACCAGUCUGAUGGGAGCAACAUAGCAUUCCCUGGGGAGCCCCGGUCUGACAAGAAAAACACAGUUCUCUUGGAAUUCUGCAUCUGCUCCUACCUCCCAGAAACUGCUCUGUUCAAGGUUACUGGUGACCUCCUGCCAGAAAAUCUAACAGCGACUUCUCAGCUCUGUUUAAAAGCCUUCAGUGGCUGCCCACUGCCUUGAGGAUAAAGUCUAAGCUUAUCUGUAGCCUCAUCUGUCCUCCCAUUUCAUACUCGACACUCCCACCAUACCAAAGGACAUUAGUUGACCCCAUCCAUGGUUUCACUUUCUGAGGUUUCAGUUACCCAUGGUCAACUGUGGCCUGAAAAUAUUAAAUGGAAAAUUCCAGAAAUAAACAAUUCAUAAGUUUUAAA